AUUGUGCUCGCUUCACGCCGGCCCAAGAUGGCGGAGGCGCUGGAGGCCCCGGGCCUGUGACUACAAAGAGGGAGUCGGGGGCCGGGCCGGACCGGAGCGCGGCGGCGGCGGCGGCGGCGGCCGAGGCCGAGGCCAGGCCCCCUCCCCUCAGCCUCCCGCCCCUCCCUCCCGCCCGCCCUCCUCCGCCCACCGGCGGCCCCGCCCCUCCCCCAACCGCCCGCCUAGCAUGGUGCGGCGGCCGCGCGCGCGGACAUGGGGGAGAAGCUGGAGCUGAGACUGAAGUCGCCCGUGGGGGCUGAGCCCGCCGUCUACCCGUGGCCGCUGCCGGUCUACGAUAAACAUCACGAUGCUGCUCAUGAAAUCAUCGAGACCAUCCGAUGGGUCUGUGAAGAAAUCCCGGAUCUCAAGCUCGCUAUGGAGAAUUACGUUUUAAUUGACUAUGACACCAAAAGCUUCGAGAGCAUGCAGAGGCUCUGCGACAAGUACAACCGUGCCAUCGACAGCAUCCACCAGCUGUGGAAGGGCACCACGCAGCCCAUGAAGCUGAACACGCGGCCGUCCACUGGACUCCUGCGCCAUAUCCUGCAGCAGGUCUACAACCACUCGGUGACCGACCCCGAGAAGCUCAACAACUACGAGCCCUUCUCCCCCGAGGUGUACGGGGAGACCUCCUUCGACCUGGUGGCCCAGAUGAUUGAUGAGAUCAAGAUGACCGACGACGACCUGUUUGUGGACUUGGGGAGCGGUGUGGGCCAGGUCGUGCUCCAGGUUGCUGCUGCCACCAACUGCAAACAUCACUAUGGCGUCGAGAAAGCAGACAUCCCGGCCAAGUAUGCGGAGACCAUGGACCGCGAGUUCAGGAAGUGGAUGAAAUGGUAUGGAAAAAAGCAUGCAGAAUACACAUUGGAGAGAGGCGAUUUCCUCUCAGAAGAGUGGAGGGAGCGAAUCGCCAACACGAGUGUUAUAUUUGUGAAUAAUUUUGCCUUUGGUCCUGAGGUGGAUCACCAGCUGAAGGAGCGGUUUGCAAACAUGAAGGAAGGUGGCAGAAUCGUGUCCUCGAAACCCUUUGCACCUCUGAACUUCAGAAUAAACAGUAGAAACUUGAGUGACAUCGGCACCAUCAUGCGCGUGGUGGAGCUCUCGCCCCUGAAGGGCUCGGUGUCGUGGACGGGGAAGCCAGUCUCCUACUACCUGCACACUAUCGACCGCACCAUACUUGAAAACUAUUUUUCUAGUCUGAAAAACCCAAAACUCAGGGAGGAACAGGAGGCAGCCCGGCGCCGCCAGCAGCGCGAGAGCAAGAGCAACGCGGCCACGCCCACUAAGGGCCCAGAGGGCAAGGUGGCCGGCCCCGCCGACGCCCCCAUGGACUCUGGUGCUGAGGAAGAGAAGGCGGGAGCAGCCACCGUGAAGAAGCCGUCUCCCUCCAAAGCCCGCAAGAAGAAGCUAAACAAGAAGGGGAGGAAGAUGGCUGGCCGCAAGCGCGGGCGCCCCAAGAAGAUGAACACUGCGAACCCCGAGCGGAAGCCCAAGAAGAACCAAACUGCACUGGAUGCCCUGCACGCUCAGACCGUGUCUCAGACGGCGGCCUCCUCACCCCAGGAUGCCUACAGAUCCCCUCACAGCCCGUUCUACCAGCUACCUCCGAGCGUGCAGCGGCACUCCCCCAACCCGCUGCUGGUGGCGCCCACCCCGCCCGCGCUGCAGAAGCUUCUAGAGUCCUUCAAGAUCCAGUACCUGCAGUUCCUGGCAUACACAAAGACCCCCCAGUACAAGGCCAGCCUGCAGGAGCUGCUGGGCCAGGAGAAGGAGAAGAACGCCCAGCUCCUGGGUGCGGCUCAGCAGCUCCUCAGCCACUGCCAGGCCCAGAAGGAGGAGAUCAGGAGGCUGUUUCAGCAAAAAUUGGAUGAGCUGGGUGUGAAGGCGCUGACCUACAACGACCUGAUUCAAGCGCAGAAGGAGAUCUCCGCCCAUAACCAGCAGCUGCGGGAGCAGUCGGAGCAGCUGGAGCAGGACAACCGCGCGCUCCGCGGCCAGAGCUUGCAGCUGCUCAAGGCUCGCUGCGAGGAGCUGCAGCUGGACUGGGCCACGCUGUCGCUGGAGAAGCUGUUGAAGGAGAAGCAGGCCCUGAAGAGCCAGAUCUCGGAGAAGCAGAGGCACUGCCUGGAGCUGCAGAUCAGCAUUGUGGAGCUAGAGAAGAGCCAGCGGCAGCAGGAGCUCCUGCAGCUCAAGUCCUGUGUGCCGCCUGACGACGCCCUGUCCCUGCACCUGCGUGGGAAGGGCGCCCUGGGCCGCGAGCUGGAGCCUGACGCCAGCCGGCUGCACCUGGAGCUGGACUGCACCAAGUUCUCGCUGCCUCACUUGAGCAGCAUGAGCCCGGAGCUCUCCAUGAACGGCCAGGCUGCUGGCUAUGAGCUCUGCGGUGUGCUGAGCCGGCCUUCGUCGAAGCAGAACACGCCCCAGUACCUGGCCUCACCCCUGGACCAGGAGGUGGUGCCCUGUACCCCUAGCCACGUCGGCCGGCCGCGCCUGGAGAAGCUGUCUGGCCUAGCCGCACCCGACUACACUAGGCUGUCCCCGGCCAAGAUUGUGCUGAGGCGGCACCUGAGCCAGGACCACACGGUGCCCGGCAGGCCGGCUGCCAGUGAGCUGCAUUCGAGAGCUGAGCACACCAAGGAGAACGGCCUUCCCUACCAGAGCCCCAGCGUGCCUGGCAGCAUGAAGCUGAGCCCUCAGGACCCGCGGCCCCUGUCCCCUGGGGCCUUGCAGCUUGCUGGAGAGAAGAGCAGUGAGAAGGGCCUGAGAGAGCGCGCCUACGGCAGCAGCGGGGAGCUCAUCACCAGCCUGCCCAUCAGCAUCCCGCUCAGCACCGUGCAGCCCAACAAGCUCCCGGUCAGCAUUCCCCUGGCCAGCGUGGUGCUGCCCAGCCGCGCCGAGAGGGCGAGGAGCACCCCCAGUCCCGUGCUGCAGCCCCGUGACCCCUCGUCCACACUUGAAAAGCAGAUUGGUGCUAAUGCCCACGGUGCUGGGAGCAGAAGCCUUGCCCUGGCCCCCGCAGGCUUCUCCUACGCUGGCUCGGUGGCCAUCAGCGGGGCCUUGGCGGGCAGCCCGGCCUCUCUCACACCUGGAGCCGAGCCGGCCACCUUGGAUGAGUCCUCCAGCUCUGGGAGCCUUUUUGCCACCGUGGGGUCCCGCAGCUCCACGCCACAGCACCCCCUGCUGCUGGCACAGCCCCGGAACUCGCUUCCUGCCUCUCCCGCCCACCAGCUCUCCUCCAGUCCCCGGCUUGGUGGGGCCGCCCAGGGCCCGUUGCCCGAGGCCAGCAAGGGAGACCUGCCCUCCGAUUCCGGCUUCUCAGAUCCUGAGAGUGAAGCCAAGAGGAGGAUUGUGUUCACCAUCACCACUGGUGCGGGCAGUGCCAAGCAGUCGCCCUCCAGCAAGCACAGCCCCCUGACCGCCAGCGCCCGUGGGGACUGUGUGCCGAGCCACGGGCAGGACAGUCGCAGGCGCGGCCGGCGGAAGCGAGCAUCUGCGGGGACGCCCAGCUUGAGCGCAGGCGUGUCCCCCAAGCGCCGAGCCCUGCCGUCCGUCGCUGGCCUUUUCACACAGCCUUCGGGGUCUCCCCUCAACCUCAACUCCAUGGUCAGUAACAUCAACCAGCCCCUGGAGAUUACAGCCAUCUCGUCCCCGGAGACCUCCCUGAAGAGCUCCCCUGUGCCCUACCAGGACCACGACCAGCCCCCCGUGCUCAAGAAGGAGCGGCCUCUGAGCCAGACCAAUGGGGCACACUACUCCCCACUCACCUCAGACGAGGAGCCAGGCUCUGAGGACGAGCCCAGCAGUGCUCGAAUUGAGAGAAAAAUUGCAACAAUCUCCUUAGAAAGCAAAUCUCCCCCGAAAACCUUGGAAAAUGGUGGUGGCUUGGCGGGAAGGAAGCCCGCGCCCGCCGGCGAGCCAGUCAAUAGCAGCAAGUGGAAGUCCACCUUCUCGCCCAUCUCCGACAUCGGCCUGGCCAAGUCGGCGGACAGCCCGCUGCAGGCCAGCUCCGCCCUCAGCCAGAACUCCCUGUUCACGUUCCGGCCCGCCCUGGAGGAGCCCUCUGCCGAUGCCAAGCUGGCCGCUCACCCCAGGAAAGGCUUUCCCGGCUCCCUGUCGGGGGCUGACGGACUCAGCCCGGGCACCAACCCUGCCAACGGCUGCACCUUCGGCGGGGGCCUGGCCGCGGACCUGAGUUUACACAGCUUCAGUGAUGGUGCUUCUCUUCCCCACAAGGGCCCCGAGGCGGCCGGCCUGAGCUCCCCGCUGAGCUUCCCCUCGCAGCGCGGCAAGGAGGGCUCGGACGCCAACCCUUUCCUGAGCAAGAGGCAGCUGGACGGCCUGGCUGGGCUGAAGGGCGAGGGCAGCCGCGGCAAGGAGGCAGGGGAGGGCGGCCUACCGCUGUGCGGGCCCACGGACAAGACCCCACUGCUGAGCGGCAAGGCCGCCAAGGCCCGGGACCGCGAGGUCGACCUCAAGAAUGGCCACAACCUCUUCAUCUCUGCGGCGGCCGUGCCUCCCGGAAGCCUCCUCAGCGGCCCCGGCCUGGCCCCGGCGGCGUCCUCCGCAGGCGGCGCGGCGUCCUCCGCCCAGACGCACCGGUCCUUCCUGGGCCCCUUCCCGCCGGGACCGCAGUUCGCGCUCGGCCCCAUGUCCCUGCAGGCCAACCUCGGCUCCGUGGCCGGCUCCUCCGUGCUGCAGUCGCUGUUCAGCUCUGUGCCGGCCGCCGCAGGCCUGGUGCACGUGUCGUCCGCUGCCACCAGACUGACCAACUCGCACGCCAUGGGCAGCUUUUCCGGGGUGGCAGGCGGCACAGUUGGAGGUGUCUUUAACCACGCGGUGCCCUCCGCCUCUGCUCAUCCGUUUGGAGCCCGUGUCGGCCGCGGGGCUGCAUGUGGCAGCGCCACACUGGGCCCGAGCCCGCUGCAGGCGGCGGCCAGCGCCUCGGCCUCUUCCUUUCAGGCCCCGGCCUCGGUUGAGACCCGGCCGCCCCCUCCGCCUCCGCCUCCGCCUCCCCCGCUGCCCCCGCCUGCGCACCUGGGCCGGUCCCCCGCGGGGCCGCCCGUCCUCCACGCCCCCCCUCCACCUAACGCCGCCUUGCCUCCUCCCCCAACGCUGCUGGCCUCUAACCCUGAGCCCGCGCUUCUGCAGAGCCUCGCGUCCCUCCCGCCUAACCAAGCUUUCUUGCCCCCCACCUCUGCUGCCUCUCUGCCGCCUGCUAACGCCUCUUUGUCUAUCAAGCUCACCUCCCUCCCGCACAAGGGCGCCCGCCCCUCCUUCACGGUGCACCACCAGCCCCUGCCCCGGCUGGCCCUGGCCCAGGCCGCGCCCGGGAUCCCACAGGCCAGCGCCACGGGGCCGUCCGCGGUGUGGGUGUCCCUCGGCAUGCCGCCUCCCUAUGCCGCGCACCUUUCGGGGGUUAAGCCGCGAUAAAGACCUUGCUUAGCUAGCAGUGCGUAUUGUGUAAGGUAAGGCCAGAGCCCUGCGCGGUGGCUCACUCCAGACACUGAACUGUCCUUCCUUUGGCAGAGAAGACGGCCACAGGGCUCGGCAGAAGUUCCGGGGGUCCUGAGGAGGGAAGAGGGAGAGAGCCAGGGAGACCAGGGAGAUGGUCGCGAGAGGAGGGACUACAGGACGGGCACCAGCCAUGGAGUGGCCUGAGUGUGUUGGGUUCCAGCUGCCCGCAGCUGGGUUCCUGCGGUGACGCCGCAGGACUGAGGCCAGCCCUGGGGGCAGCUGUGCCAGCCCCUGUGGGCGAGGCUCACGGGGUGCCAGGCCAGGGGGCUGGGAGCUCUAGCUCCUAGAGCAGUCUCCAGGGCUCCAUCCGCACCAGGCCCAGGUCACUCAUGACGGGUGGCGUGGCUUGGUGCUGUUCCCCAGGCGCCCAGCAUGUAGCAGGCACGGUGCCGGCUGCAGAGGUCCUGGAGAGCCAGGGUGGCUGGCUGGAUGCCUCUGGUCGGGGCUGUCUGGCCAGUAGCCUCGGAUGCCCUCAUAGGGAGCCAGUGAAGCCCCAAGUGCCCUGCCUGCCUGGGGGCUGAUGGGUUCCCGGCGGGGUCGAGAGGCAAGCUCUGUGCCCUGCGUGUUGAGGCCCCCUUGCUGGACACGGCUGAUGGCCACACUGCCCUGUGGUCAUGGCCCACAGCCGAGGGGCUUUCAGCUGCUCAGAUGUCAGCACCAAGCUGGGCAGGUUAGUGUAGACGGUGCCCACCUUUGAGACCAGAAGGAAGUUGGAAGCAGGAGUGAUUUUGAUGAUGUGAGGCCUUCAGGGAAUGUCCUGUUCACUCCUCCCCCAAGAGGCUGUGGAGACUGUGGCCGCUGACCCCUGAGGGCAGUUGGCCACCCGUGCCCUCCAGGGACAUGGCGUGCCUGGCGGCGUAGUGCAAAGGUGCCCUCUGCUUGCCCCUGGCCUUCUGCCUCAGGGGCCCCUGGGACACAGGCCUUCCUGGGCGAGUCCAAAGCCCACCGGGCAAGGAGAGGAGGACUGGGAGCCAGGAGCCAAGGCGGAGGCUGUGGCCAGGGCUGGUCAGCCUGGCGGGUCAAUGCGGGCACCUGCGGGCUGGACAAGCUAUGCUGGGUCUCUUAGGAGAUGAGCUGCAGGUAGGGUGGCUUUAGCUGGACUCGGCUGUGUGUCUCCUUUGGAGGAAGGCUGGAGCUUGGCCGGCGUGUCCAGGUGUCAGGCUCCCUGGUCUGUCACGGGGCACGCCCGUCGUCUGUUGUGGUUAGAGGAGCUGGCACUAUGCCUGUCAUGGUGCUGGCCCCAGGUGGCGUGUGUGCUCGUGGGAGGCCUCGGUCCCCAGCCUGGGUGAGUGUUGGGCUCCCCCAGGCGCGAUGGUAACCUCAGGCCGCUCUUCCCGCUGUGCCCUUCUGCAGGUAACUAGGAUUUCUACCUCAACCGCGAGACCUAUGCAAGGACGGUGUGGACCAACUCGCGCCCGCGGCAUGGUGCCCGCCGGCCUGCCGGGCUCCCACCCCUGGACGGCAGAGGCAAGGACGGACGGGAGCUCCACUGUGAAUCGGCGGCACGCGCCGCAGGAGGCUGGGACUGGUCCAGUUUGUACUGUCGAUAGUUUUAGAUAAAGUAUUUAUCAUUUUUUAAAAAGUAUAAACAAUUCUGACUUAUUUUAUUCCAUCUAAGUGGUAAAAGGCAACUUAUUGAGAAAUAUAAAUAUCUAUAUAUGAGAGCUCUAUAUAAAGACACGUGUCUGCAGGGCGGGCCCGCCAGCGGAUUCGCCACAGCCUGCCCCGGUGCUAUCUCGUCCCCAGGCCCGCGCCUGCCUCCACCCGCUUGGUGCUGACUAGACGCUGACAACGCCGAACCCCGUUCUCGGAAACGCCGCCCGGCCGGCUCCCCCGACGCGCUGCUCCCGUACCAAAGGCAGGCCCGUCGCCACCACAUUCCUCGGAGGCCUCCCCGCGGCCUGAGCCCCUUCCUGAGCGCCCUGGCGCCUGCCCUGAGCUCUUCACCUUUACCCCGGCACUGUGAACCCCCAGACUGUUCACCCUCCGGGGCGUGGGUUGCGCCCUUGCAUGUGAAGGGGCCUGCGCGGUGACGCAGCUGGCCAUGUGCUGCGCGAUGGUGCUGUGAGGACGGCGCGGGCACGUUGAACAAGUGCAUUUACUUUUGUAUUUCUCGGCUGUCCAUGGCUCGCAGCAUGCCCUGCGAUGCGGGGCAGGCCUGUCGUGGGUCCCUUGGUGUUUCUGUACAGGAGAGAGUCACACUAAUGAGUGGCAGUAUUUUAUAGAGAUGUGAUGAGAAUUUAUAAAUUUCAUAGAUUUGACAGCUUUUAUUUUUAGAUGGUAUAAUGCACAGUGAAGAGGAAAGAAAAGCGAGGGGAAAAAACCUUAUUUAUUCAAACAGUGCACAAAAUGGCCCCAGCGUCAGCCCCGACCCUAGACCCCUCAGUUGCAGCUCCCAGCAGCCCAGACAGAGCUGCCGGCGCCCCUGCCUGCCCCACAUCCCUUCCUGUCAGGGCCACGCCUGGCACCCAUCCCUUGGAGCCUGUGCUGGUUCUCCCAGCUGCUGUGGGUGUGCUGGGGCCAGGGUGCACUGCUGAAACCUGGCCUCUCUGGCCCUAGGCCCCAGGGUGACGUCGGCCCCCCACUCUGCAGCCUUGGCGGGUGCCUGGGACUGGGUGUGGAAGGAGAGGAGCUGAGGCCGGGGUGUAGCAGGCAGGCAGGGCCACUCCAGUGCUUCUGGAGCCCUGAGCAGUCAGGGCCUGGGUUGUCUGAGCAGUGGUGGCUCUGUGCCCUCCCUGGAGGAUGGGAUCUGGGAGUCUGAGCUCCCCGCAUCUGGCCCUGGGCUGUGUGGCACUUGCUGAGCCCACCUUCUCAAGUGCUUGCUCCUGUGAGAUGGCAUCGGGGAGCCCCUUCCCCAAGGUGCCACAGAUCCACCCUCCAGGGAGCUGCCAGCCCUGUGUUCUGGUUCCCAAGGGCAGGAUGGACACACGUCACAUCCCUACCACGUGGCCUCCAAAGGGAGCCACGGAGGAAAGGCUUCUGUGGUUGCUAGGUGGGGGAGUCCUGUGUGGGAGGGCCUGAAGACCCCUGCUUGUGCCUGGUGAGGGGGGUGCUGCCUCCCCCAGCCCCCAACAACCUCUCAGACCCCCACCCUCCAACAUAGCUGAGUUCUGAAGAUGGUGCUCCGGACCUGUCCUCUUAAGUGGUGCCCAGUGCCCUCCCCACCCCACGUUGGUGCUCUCAGCUAGAAGGUGCUGUGCCUCUGCCUGAGCCCCAAGCCCCGAGCCUGGCCUUCAGGACAGGCAGCCUGCUCUGUGUCGCCACGGGCCGGAUACGCCACAGGGUUGAUGGCAGAGACGGCCGAGUCCCUGGUCUAGAACAAGACACAUUCUUUAAACACUGUAUUACUUCUGCCUCCCUCUAGGUGACAGUGGCAGUCCGGGUGCCAUCACGGGUCCUGCAGAUGGCCAUGCAGGGCUCCUGCCCACGCAGGCCACCGUAUGUUCAGGACACGCACUGGGUCUCAGAGCCACUGGCCCAGGCAGAAGUCUCCUUGAGCCCACUGGGUCAUAUGCGUGUCACCACACGUGAACUAGUGUGGUGGCUGCCUGCGGACACCCUCCUGUUCUGAGCCCUGGGCCUGUGUUCUUCUCAGACACUCCCAGACUGAGGGGUGGUGUGUGGCGGGUGGCAGGGUGGCUGUGGAGACUGGGGAUCUGGAGCCUGGUGCUGGCACCUGGCCUGAGUUUCCGUGGGCAGCUGGCGGGGACCUGUGCUGCUGCUGCUGACUGUGGGUGGGCGGGCGGCGCCUGGGAGUGGCUCUUGCUCAGGAAUUGAUAGGAACCCUAAAAACUAGGAUACCCCCUCCUCGGCCCAUGAGGCACGCACAGUGACUUAUUUAAGACUUCCCCCUUAAUUUAUCUGCCCCCAGGAUGCGUCAGUCUGUUCAGUGGUCAGCAGGCCCCCCACCCCCCGCCGACUGCCCUCGCCAUCGUGGUCAGACCCCCCUCCCAACACAACACGCUGCUGGUCUGUGUCAGCCUUUGUAACGUGGGAGGCUCUGCCGUGUCUUCCGGGUGAACUGUAUUUGGAUUGCGCGCAUUGUCACGGUCCGCCCCUGGGCUGCAGGCGCCCCUUCCUCUGGGCACCCCUGCAUUCUGCAUCCCCACCUCUAGACGCUGUAAUAAACAGACUGUUUUCACUCGGA